AGAAGGACGCAGGCAGCAAAGAGUAGUCAGUCCCUUCUUGGCUCUGCUGACACUCGAGCCCACAUUCCAUCACCUGCUCCCAAUCAUGCAGGUCUCCACUGCUGCCCUUGCCGUCCUCCUCUGCACCAUGGCUCUCUGCAACCAGGUCCUCUCUGCACCACUUGCUGCUGACACGCCGACCGCCUGCUGCUUCAGCUACACCUCCCGACAGAUUCCACAGAAUUUCAUAGCUGACUACUUUGAGACGAGCAGCCAGUGCUCCAAGCCCAGUGUCAUCUUCCUAACCAAGAGAGGCCGGCAGGUCUGUGCUGACCCCAGUGAGGAGUGGGUCCAGAAAUACGUCAGUGACCUGGAGCUGAGUGCCUGAGGGGUCCAGAAGCUUCGAGGCCCAGCGACCUCAGUGGGCCCAGUGGGGAGGAGCAGGAGCCUGAGCCUUGGGAACAUGCGUGUGACCUCCACAGCUACCUCUUCUAUGGACUGGUUAUUGCCAAACAGCCACACUGUGGGACUCUUCUUAACUUAAAUUUUAAUUUAUUUAUACUAUUUAGUUUUUAUAAUUUAUUUUUGAUUUCACAGUGUGUUUGUGAUUGUUUGCUCUGAGAGUUCCCCCUGUCCCCUCCACCUUCCCUCACAGUGUGUCUGGUGACAACCGAGUGGCUGUCAUCGGCCUGUGUAGGCAGUCAUGGCACCAAAGCCACCAGACUGACAAAUGUGUAUCAGAUGCUUUUGUUCAGGGCUGUGAUCGGCCUGGGGAAAUAAUAAAGAUGUUCUUUUAAACGGUAAA